CCCCCCCCCGCCCUCCCCCUCCUUUUUCUGUGUGGCUGGCUGUGUGACGUUUUCUGUCCCGGACGAGGCCCUGAGGGAACAUGGCAGGAGGAGGUGGAACUAGGUGGAACUCACUUGACAGCAAACCCAUUUUGUGGCACUGGGACAGGCAGGUGUGCGCAGGUGCCUGCGGUGAACUGCUGUGCUCGUCAGACAGAGGGACAGCUCACUGUAGGCACUGUCCACCUCCUGUUUCCGCAGACCGGGAGCACCUGGAAGUAGGCUGAUUGGUGAGUGCGCAGUGGCUUCUUGUCCAGUCGCAGAGAAAGAAGGGAUGAAAACCCAGCACGGGCUUCCCUGCUCUGGAGGAAACUCUCCUUAGAGUUCCCCUUUUCAGCUCUUUGUUGCCUGUGUCUCAUGUGACCAUCCCACGGUCUCGAGUGACACUGCUGGCAGGUUGGUAGAAUCAGGGAGGCUCGCUCCUGACCUGUGGGCACCCCUAGCAGUGUCUGUCACCACAGUAACCCGGUAUACACAAGGCUUCAGCCACCACAGAGACCAUGGUUGGAAGUGUUGUCAGCAGCCUGGAAGAGUGAAAGCUCUUAGAUGCGGGUCACCCGACCCGGGACAGAAAGAGGGGAUCCCCGAGGAGCUGUUGAAUGAGGAAGCACCUUUAAAAGUCCAAAUGCUGUGUCAGUGUAAAGUAUGAAUAAUAGAGAAUGCAAUGUCUUGCCAUUGGGGACUGUCAAGGGGGAAAGCGUGUCACAGCCCGCCUAGUCAGGGGCCCAGUUUUCCCUUCCCACUGUAGCUCUUUCUUCUUUGCCAUGGGCUGUUUCUGGAACCACAGCUCCGGCUACACAGGGCGGCCCCCUUCCCUUUGAUGGCUGGUUUUACAGGAAGUGCGUCUCCCUUCCCGAGUGUUCCGUCCUUCAAGGUGUGUCACACAUAGCUGUGUGCAGUUAGAGCCUGUGUCAGAGAGCUCUCCUCCUGGAUUCUUCCUAGGUCCUUAUUGUGUAACCUGGAGCAGUGAUAAGUUGUCACCAUCAUGAAUGCAUCGCAUAGCUUCAGAAACUGGGAGUGAUUUGGGAGAGAGAAGCAUACUUAGUUGAAGCAAACCAAAUACUGAGGAGCAAUAAAGCUUCACAAGAAGUAGAUUAGCAGAGUGAGCUGGUGCCAUGUGACAGCACAGGAUCUCCAAACAAUGCAGCUCAGAAGGGAACAGCAGGUCUUCAGAUGAAGUCUCUCAUUCUGCGGAUGAGAAAAGUGAGGCCUGAGAAGUGAAGCGGCUUGCCAGUAAGCCCUCCUCCUGGUUGGUGGCAGAACUGGGUCUAGAACAGCCUCCAGCCAGCUGCAGCCCCCGCUCCCCAGCACAUCCCCGGAGGGGCCUGAUCUGCAGUAGUGGGACGGCUCUGCACUGACCCCUGGGUGUGUUUCUAAAGAGUCACUCUAACGACUAAUUGUACAGCCGCUGUCUUGCCAUGGAAUGGCACCUUUUAAAAACAUCCAUCUAGUUUCUUUUAAUUUUCUAUAUUUUAACAAGAGAGCUAAAAAUCUCCAUAGUGAAAGGCCAGGUCUAGGGAGCGUCAUUUCCUAGAAGGGGAAGCAGUAUGAAUCAGGAGUUUUAAGCAAACAUCCCUCAUUCUGAUGUUUUUUAUUCACAAAGACAUUUCACACAGAAAAGAAAACUCAAUUAUGCUGCAAACACAUCCUAUUUUAUUUUAUUUUUUAAUAAGGCAUGUUCUGGAGCCACUUUGAAUCUCCACAGUGCUUCCUUUUAUUAGAGAAGCUGGAUGUGGAUCUGUCGCAGAGCCUGGGUCGGGAGAGGCCGCCCUGUCCCUGGUGUGAAUGUCACUCUGACAGCCUUGUUAGUUUGGUCUUUGAAUAUGACAUUGUGUUAAAGAAUUGUACAAUGGAUAAUUCUGGGGGCAGAACUCUUAAAAGCCUUUUAAUGAGAAUAUCCCUGAAUUUGCUGCCAACAAUUGCUUUCCCAUGAGGCUCUAAUGGAAACAGUACACAAAGCUCCCAUAAGUCAGCCCAGCAGCCCGGCCAGAGACUCACACAGACCCCGCCGGACUAACUGGGGGAAAGACAACAUGGACACCUUCAUGCAGACUGAGGCAGGGCUGGAGCUGGAGGUCCUGCCGGCAGCUUUCUUUGCUCCCUUCUACAUUUCCCUUGAAAUAACCACGGAUUUUGCCCUCAGGCCAACCACGACUCUACCUGUGUGGAUCCCCUUUAGCUCUCUGCCCGUAGCUCCUCAGGGGUGUGGGAGGGGGCCCAAUAGCACACCUAGUAUCAGCGACAUCAAAGAAGAAACUUUUCCAAAUUUAAGCAGAAAAAGGAUUUGUUCCUCAAGCUGCACUUACAAAAUGCCUCUGUGUCUUCUGCCUUAUGGAUUUUUAUAUUUGAGGAAAGAGGAAAGAAGAUAAGUGAUUAUUUUGAAAGAUUGAGGCAUUUUGGCCCGACCAAAACUGUGACUACUACUCAUAGUUGUACCAGCAGCAGCAGUUGUAACGCUAAAGAGGAGAAAAAGAAGUGCAUUCUUACACAUGACACAUGUUAGCAGAUUGCAAAUCUGGGCAGUGGAGGAGCCCUGCUGCUCAGACACCACCAUUCACUAAACCUGGGAAAGGGGCGGCCUCUCCAAGGCCGGCAUUCUUAUAAACAGCCACAGCCAGAGCAAACUGAAGUCAGAACCCACGGACACCCACUGACACAUCAAUGCAACCACGCAAAAAUGAACUGCUAAAAAAACACUUCAGGACGAGUGUUUCUGCUGCCUGCUCUUCUCAGGAGAUAUUAGCGAGAUGCUCACACUGUGCACUGGACUCUUCCCUGACUUCACUCCCUGGGGUUCCCAUCAAAUGUGAGACAAUCACAUUUGUUAAGAGAGAGUGGUGUGUAGAAUGGUUUGGAAUGUGCGAGGCACCUUAAAAAUAGUCCUGAAUGAGAAGUAGCCAUGCACGGACGCUGGUCAGAUUUCAGGUAUAAAGGAGACCAGGCCUGUGCCCAGAGGAUUGAGUUUCUGGGUCAGAAAUCUCAAAGAGCUCUUCUCCUCAGUGCCUGCUUUUAUCCUUCAAUCAAGGAAGCACACAAAGCACUCACAAUCCCACGUGCCUCAGCUGUGAAAUGCCAGCCACAAGGAAGUUACGUGGGGUUUUAUGCCAAGUAUUUGCACUCAUGUGUUGGCCUCAUGUACUGCUUUUGAAAUAAGUGGUUGCAAAACUGGCCAGGACAAAAUGGAACCCUCCAGAAAAUGAAGCCAUGGUCAUGGUGAUGGAAUUGUCCUAAUAGAGGAGUAGCAUUGCUAGGCACUCUAGUGAUGGCCAUGAAAAGCCUUCCUUUUCUGUUUGUGUUUGAGAUUGUGAAGUUAUCUUCUUAAGUGUGGGAAGUAAUUUGUAAGCCACUUUCUCUGGAGGUAGGGAAGUUAGCCUUUGUCAAUCAGUGUGGGAUGCAGCUCUAUUGGGGAAGACAUGGACGGGAGUUCCGGAACACUGACGUGGGGAGAAUGGUUACAAUUGUCAAGACUAGUGUCUCAGCAGCCUCGGAAACAAGUGAGGGUGGUGGUGGUUUAGAUAAGCUGCUUUAAUAGGGAGAUCAAGAUGAAUUUGAUGUAUAAUCAGAAUCCUAGCUCAGGGGCCCCCCCGUUUUACCUGAGCAGAGUGUAUCCAUAGAGGAGCUACAGGGUCAGCUCGUGCAGGCGGCCAGACUGCAUCAAGAGGAGACAGAGACAUUUACAAACAAGAUCCAUAAGAUGGAGGAGGAGCACCUCUAUGCCUUGAGGUGGAAAGAACUGGAAAUGCACAGCCUGGCUUUGCAAAACACCCUCCAUGAGCGAACCUGGAGUGAUGAGAAGAAUCUGAUGCAGCAGGAGCUCCGGUCCUUGAAGCAGAACAUUUUCCUCUUCUACGUCAAACUCAGGUGGCUGCUGAAACACUGGCGGCAAGGGAAGCAGAUGGAGGAGGAAGGAGAGGAGUUCACUGAGGGUGAACAUCCAGAGACCCUCUCCAGGCUCGGGGAGCUUGGAGUCCAGGGGGGUCACCAGGCGGAUGGCCCAGACCACGACAGUGACCGAGGCUGUGGCUUUCCAGUGGGGGAGCACUCCCCACACUCCCGGGUGCAGAUUGGAGAUCACAGCUUGCGGCUGCAGACCGCGGACAGGGGACAGCCCCACAAACAGGUGGUGGAAAACCAGCAGCUGUUCAGCGCCUUCAAGGCCUUGCUGGAGGACUUCCGUGCGGAGCUGCGGGAGGAUGAGCGUGCCCGACUACGGCUGCAGCAGCAAUAUGCCAGCGACAAGGCGGCCUGGGACGUGGAGUGGGCCGUGCUCAAGUGCCGUCUGGAACAGAAUUGUUGUGGAUAUCCCAGAAUUAACAUUGAGGAGGAGACUUUAGGCUUCACCAGGCUGCCAGCUGGGUCCACGGUAAAAACGUUGAAGAGCCUUGGGUUGCAGAGAUUGGAGCUGGAAGAGAAGACUGAGAACAAGUUGGGAGAACUAGGCUCCUCCGCUGAGAGCAAGGGGGCCUUGAAGAAGGAGAGAGAGGUGCACCAGAAGCUCCUGGCAGACAGUCACAGCCUGGUCAUGGACCUGCGCUGGCAGAUCCAUCACAGCGAGAAGAACUGGAACCGGGAGAAGGUGGAACUUCUCGACCGCCUGGACAGAGAUCGGCAGGAGUGGGAGCGGCAGAAGAAGGAAUUCUUGUGGAGGAUAGAGCAGUUGCAGAAAGAGAACAGUCCCCGGAGAGGUGGCAGUUUCCUCUGUGAUCAAAAAGACGGCAACGUUCGCCCCUUUCCCCACCAGGGAAGCCUCCGCAUGCCCCGUCCAGUGGCCAUGUGGCCUUGUGCAGAUGCUGACUCCAUCCCGUUUGAAGACCGGCCGCUGUCCAAGCUGAAGGAGUCGGACAGGUGCUCGGCCAGUGAGAAUCUCUACCUGGAUGCCUUGUCCCUGGAUGACGAGCCAGAAGAGCCACCAGCCCACAGGCCCGAGAGGGAGUUCAGGAACCGCCUCCCUGAGGAAGAAGAAAAUCACAAAGGAAAUCUUCAAAGGGCGGUGUCCGUGUCCUCCAUGUCUGAGUUCCAGCGUCUAAUGGACAUCUCCCCCUUCCUGCCUGAGAAGGGCCUGCCGUCCACCAGCAGCAAGGAGGAUGUCACCCCACCCCUGUCUCCAGACGACCUCAAGUACAUCGAGGAGUUCAACAAGAGCUGGGACUACACACCCAACAGGGGCCACAAUGGUGGGGGGCCGGACCUUUGGGCCGACAGGACCGAGGUGGGGCGGGCAGGGCACGAGGACAGCACAGAGCCUUUCCCCGACUCCUCCUGGUACCUAACCACAAGUGUCACCAUGACCACGGACACCAUGACCAGCCCAGAGCACUGCCAGAAGCAGCCACUGCGGAGCCACGUCCUCACCGAGCAGUCGGGGUUGCGCGUGUUACACAGCCCGCCUGCCGUGCGCAGGGUCGACAGCAUCACGGCGGCAGGUGGUGAGGGUCCCUUUCCCACAAGCAGAGCCAGAGGGAGCCCGGGAGACACCAAGGGAGGCCCUCCAGAACCCAUGCUCAGCAGGUGGCCUUGCACCUCCCCCAGGCACUCCCGGGACUAUGUGGAGGGGGCACGGCGCCCCCUUGAUAGUCCCCUCUGUACCUCCCUGGGGUUUGCCUCCCCACUGCACAGCCUGGAGAUGUCCAAGAACUUGAGUGAUGACAUGAAGGAGGUGGCCUUCUCUGUCAGGAAUGCCAUCUGCUCCGGCCCUGGCGAGCUGCAAGUCAAGGACAUGGCCUGCCAGACCAAUGGGUCCCGGACGAUGGGGACCCAGACUGUUCAGACCAUCAGUGUGGGCUUGCAGACUGAAGCCCUGCGUGGCAGCGGUGUCACCAGCAGCCCCCACAAGUGUCUCACUCCAAAGGCUGGGGGCGGUGCUACACCCGUGUCGUCUCCUUCCCGGAGCCUUAGGAGCAGACAGGUGGCCCCUGCCAUCGAGAAGGUGCAGGCCAAGUUUGAACGCACAUGCUGCUCCCCCAAGUAUGGUUCUCCCAAGCUGCAGAGGAAGCCCCUCCCCAAAGCCGACCAGCCAAAUAACAGGACGUCACCAGGGAUGGCCCAGAAAGGGUACAGUGAGUCAGCCUGGGCCCGCUCCACCACCACAAGGGAGAGCCCCGUGCACACCACCAUUAAUGAUGGCCUCUCCAGCCUCUUCAACAUCAUUGACCACAGCCCCGUGGUGCAGGACCCCUUCCAGAAGGGGCUGCGGGCCGGCAGUCGGUCUCGCUCAGCAGAGCCCCGACCAGAGCUGGGCCCAGGCCAGGAAACAGGCACCAAUUCCCGAGGAAGGUCGCCUAGCCCCAUUGGGGUGGGGUCAGAGAUGUGCAGGGAGGAAGGGGGAGAGGGCACGCCAGUGAAGCAGGACUUAUCUGCUCCCCCUGGCUACACGCUCACUGAGAACGUGGCCCGGAUCCUCAACAAGAAGCUGCUGGAACAUGCCUUAAAGGAGGAGAGGAGGCAGGCUGCCCACGGGCCCCCGGGUCUCCACAGUGACAGCCACUCGCUGGGGGACACAGCCGAGCCAGGGCCCAUGGAGGAACUACCUUGUUCUGCACUAGCUCCAUCCCUAGAGCCCUGCUUCUCCAGGCCCGAGAGACCAGCAAACCGUCGCCCUCCGUCCCGUUGGGCCCCACAUUCCCCCACUGCCUCACAGCCUCAGUCACCCGGAGACCCGACGUCCUUGGAGGAGCAUGGUGGCGAGGAGCCGCCCGAGGAGCAGCCACACCGAGAUGCAAGCUUGCAUGGAUUAUCACAGUAUAAUUCACUGUAAUUUGCAUAACCACACCAUCACCAUGAACAAAACUCUGCCCAACAGGAGAGAUCUAGUUUUCUCAAGGUCAAAGAAUGUUUUUUAAAAACACAAAGCUGCUGAAUGUUCAACCUGUGAAACUGAGAUGUUUCUAGAAUGAAACAGUAAAUGUGCCUGUAAUAACUUAAUUUUUUUCAUAGCUCAGAAAACUAUUUUUGUCUCCAUCUUUUUUACACACAGUAUAUUAAACGAAAAGGUAAAUAAGGUAUAAAUAGAUUUAAAAAAUAAAAGUUUUAAAAAAUGUACAUUUUAAGAGAUUCUGAACACCCUCGCUGUCAAUACCUGACUGCCUCUGUUAAAUUUGCACUGUUACAUUUUGGUUCAGUUUAUUUCCAUGUUGAAUUAGAGUGGAUUAAGUUAAUUUUAUUUUGUCAGUGUUACUGUUUUUUACGAAUUUUUUAAUGCUUCAGACUGUCUGAUUCAGUGAACUUUUUGUAGUGAAAAAGCCAUGAAGCCAGUAGACAAGACAGAUAUUCUGUAUGCUGGAGGGGAUACAGGAUGAUUUUGAAAAGGUACAAAGUCCUCAGUGGGCUUAGAAAAUUCACUGUAUGAUCCUUAUAUUAUCCUACUUGGCUUGCACGUCUUCGGGUGCAUGUAUAUACCGCUACUGUGUCCUCGCCAUCACCUAAAUGUGACUCAGUCUGUUCCACUGUAAUAUGUUGUGAAUUUCCUUGUACUGUACUUUUAUUGUUGGUCUUCUUGCAUCGAUGAUCCAACAGCAACACCAUUUUUAAAUUAUUGUGAAAAGAUUAACUGGCAAUGUACAGAGUUUACUCAAAGUUUUCUUAAGGGAAAACACUACAAAAAGUCACAAGGAUACCAAAUGGAAACACAUGAUGAUGCCUCUGGGUCUGUAUGAGACCGUGAUGAAGUAGAAAUAAAGCCCUUCUGAGAUGGCA